GCUAUUGAGCAUCUUAUUUUCUUGAACCCUCAGGCUUAUGAAGAGCAGAGCCAAAUGGAGAAAGAAUUCUUCCAUCAGAACAUCCCCAAGCAGUUUUUGAAUUUGUAAAUAAAUGUGGCCUGGAAAAUCCAGGCAUCUAAAGAUAAUGCUGGGUUUCAAUUAAACCGGUCAGUUUUUCAAAUAGUUGUUAUAAUGUGUGUGUUUAUUUUUUUGGUUGUAUCUAUGAGACUUUGUUUCACACAAAAACUGAUAAACACAGGAAAAGUGUCAAGAGGCAAAGGAGAAAAGAAGAUGAGAGAGAGAGAUAAAACCAACAGAAAUGGAGGUUGGAUAUAGUAAUUGCCCUAGUGAGAAAUUUGCAUGGGAGAAAAGUUGACAAUAAGGACAGCCUAUGAUAUGGUGACACAAGAGAAUAGUUAUUAGUGAGUUCAGAGAAAAGUUUCCAAGUAGCCACCUCUGUCUUACUAUAAUAUUCCCAAGGCAUCAGUGAGACAGGCUAAAACCACAAGGACUAGUUCAGCAGUAUAGAGGAAAAUGGGGUGAGAGGAGGCUUUAAUAUGAUAGUGAGCUUAAUCAUUUAGAGAUGUCACAACAUUUAGAAGUAUAUUCUUUGUAUAACGUUAUAUAGUAGCUUGGCAUGGCAGAGAAGUAAUUUGAUGUAUUGCUAAGGCAGCUUUUUCCCCCACUUAUUAAAUUUAAAAAAAUUAUAUGGAAAGCCCUAUUGGUAAAUCUUUAGUUAAUUACAAAUUGAUGUCUCAAAUAUGAUUUAUCUCAAUGAAAUAAGAAGCCAAUAGUAUUUUGGAAACUGAACUAUUUAUCACACAGGUUUAUCAAAUGAUCCAAAAUAUGUAACUGUUUUAGAAUUAUGAAGUUCUAUGAAAAUAUAAAGAUGAUAAAAUAUUUUCUUGGCCUGAAAAAAUUUACAGCAUAAAAAGUGGAUGUGAAGACAUAUUUGAUAUAUAUCUUUCAAAUGUUAUCUUUUAUUUCAGAUGUUAUCUUCUAUUUGAAGAUUUUUGUUGUUUUGCCUUUAGAGUCCUCAUUCAGAUUUCUGUUGCCUGAAAAGUAACUAGCUUUCUGGUUUUUGAAAAGAUAAUAUGCUUUUUGAAGCAAAAAGUUUUUUUGAUUAUUUGAGGAGCAUCCCUUUUAAUUUUCUGAAGCAGUUGUAAGGAUGUUUGUUGCUAAAAAUAAGUCAGCUAGGAAUUGCUAAAGAGUCUUAGCAUCAUGUGUUCUGACAAGGCAUAGAAGAGAUCUCAAGGAAAAUAAUGCAGAAAUCAAGCUGAGAAGGCUCUGAUUAGAUGGAACCAACUUGAGAAUGUUUUAUGAAACUAUAUCAGGAUCAAUCUUCCUUGCACAGAUAACAGGAAAGGCCAAAGUGACAGUAUUCAAAAAAAGAUAUAUGUUUAUUUCUUAUUCAUAUAAAACUCAUCUGCUGCCAGCAAUUUUAGGCUGGUAUAGUGACGCCGCAGAUUAUAGGGAGCCACACUUUUUUAAAGUCUUGGCAUUUCAAGCUUCACCAUGAUUUGCAAUUCUAGUCAGCAGAACAGAGUCUGUUAAUUUUGGAAAGUUUGUUCUAACUUUGAUUUUAAUUUUGUUUUUCCAUUGUUGAACUUAAAAACACAAUUAAGUUUUGUAUGUUGAUUUUAUAUCUUUUGACCUUGCUAAAUUCUCACUUAUUAAUUCUAAUAGUUGCUUUACACAUUUCUUAGGAUUUUAUUUGCAGUCGUGUCAUCUGCAAAUGAAAAUAAUUUUAGUUCUUUUAAAUCUUUAUGCCCUUUAUUUGUUUUUCUUGCCUUCUUGCAACACCUCCAAUUAGGUAUUAACUGGAAGUGAUGAGAAGAGAACAUCUUCAUCUUGUUCUGUAUCUCAGGAAGAAAUACAUAUUUCAUCUUUAAGUUUGAUGUCACCUGUGGGUUUUUGGGUUUUGGUAGAUGCCUUUUAUAUCCCAUUGAAUAAUUUCUCUUUUACUCUUAGUUUGCCAAGAAUUUUUGUUCUUGUUUUUUUGCUUUUACUAAUCAUGAAUGGACACUGAUUAUUUAUAGCACUUGACUUUUAGUAUAUGUUUAUUGUCUGUUUCCUUCAUAAGGCAUUAUUUCUGUCUUGUACACUAUUGUAUACUGAGAUUCUAAUACACUACCUUAUGCUCAGUAUGUAGUCAGUAAAUAAAUACAUGUUACGUGAAUGAAUUAUUAAAUCAGAGUUGCUUGAUCAGAAAAGAUCUGACUCAAGAGAAAACUUGCCCGUUAGUGCUGAAUCUGCAUAAUCUGACACUCUACUGCCACCUGGUGAUAGUAUAUCUAAAUUGCAAUAAAAGCUUCUCAGGAGGUGAAUAAGCAUGUGAGCUAAAACUGCAAAUGAUUGGACUGACGUGGCAAUUAUAAUUUAAAAAUAUACAUAUACUCAUGAUAUGUAUCUGGACUGCAUUUGAGAUUUAGCACAUAUAUUUCACAUUUAAAAGAUGCUGAAAUGUUUUCUGUUUUCCUGACUGCUAGGAAAGAAUGAAGUGGAUCAGUUAAAUUACAUAUGUUAAAGAAAUAGAAUAAAUUGGGAAAGUUGGCAGAAGUAGAGUAAGAGCAAAGGCACAUUUUCUAUAUUUGAAUUCCUGCUCUGUAAGCAUUUUCUUGCUGUAAGGUGCUAGCUAAAUUUUAAUUUUAAAGAACAAGAAUUUUUAACUUCUUAAUAUCUUGUAUUAAUAUUUAAUAUAUUGCAAGAAAAUCCAGCUUGUGGCCAAGAAUGAAAUUUAAUGCUUGUUCUUAAAAAUUAAAUCCUUUAGUUACACAGAAUUCACUGAGAUUUAAGUGUAGAAUACAAUGGGAUUUCUGUUAUAUUAGACAGUUUCUUGGAAUGAAAUCAUCUAUCAUCUACACUGUUAUGAUUACCACUAUAUACUUUCAUUUCUUAGCCUCUCUCCGAAAAAACAAACCAUGUGCCAAAUAUAUGUUAGUAAAAGUUUUUAGAGAUGCAAUUCAAAUAUUAAAAUUUUCUUAUUGGUGUUAAAAUGGUCAAUCUUGUAAAAUGUUGAUAAUUUUACAUAAAGGUUAGCCCUUCUCAUGAUCAAAAUACCCUGAGAUGAUAGUGUUGGAAGUACUGUUUUAGUAAUAAAGAUUAUCAUGUGGGUAAGUUCCCUACAAGGCCCAUGAUGGUAAUGCCCCUAGAUUUUGUCUUCAAAGAAAACUGCUGAGAGGCAAUAAUUUUUUUUGUAUGUGUCCCAUUUUCAUUAAUGCAUGGUAAUUGAUGGAGUUGCAGUGACUUGUAGCAGUAAUGAGUUCUAAACAUAAUAAUGCACUCUUUUCUAAUAAGUGAGCACUGCUGGUGUUUAAGAGCAUACUAAAUCAGUUGCUUUAGUAUGAAUUUAUUAGUUUUUUUCAGCAUUAGUUUUAAUAGUAGUUAUUUACAUAAGCGUACAUCCCAUUAACCGCCAUCAGGGCUGGAAAACAUGCUGAACUGUUCAUAUUUUCAUAUAAUUAUUGAACAUAAUGGUUUCAUUUGCAUUUCUAAACAGUGAUGUUUCUGUCAGCCUUGGAAAUAGUGUCUUUACGCAGUCCCUAUUUCACAUCCACUUAUUUGACAUCGUUAAAUUUUAUGCUAAUGUGCUUCCCUAGAAUAUCAUCAGUAGGACAGAUGCUUGUGCUUUAAUAUACAAAUCAGGGAUGCUUUUCCAUCCCCUAAAUGGCAAAGGAAAUUUUAAAAAAUCCACACUUUUAGAUACAGAGCCUGUCUCUAUAUAAAUGGGUUUAUGAAAUAAAACUUCCACGGUUAAAUGUUAUAAUCUGGUUGUCUCUUCAAAAUGCUUCAUUAUGAAUAACUAUAUACCUGACUAGGUUUGGUUUUGUUGUCUUGAAUGAAGAGGUGAAUCUUGAUAAAUAUCAUGUUCCUUAUGAAUAUUUAGAGUUCUGCUUCUGAAAUGUUGAUCUUGAGAUGCGAGUUUUUCAGUGGCUUUGAAUAUGUCGGGCCACAGUGUUAGUUCUUAAAGUAUUCUCUAUAUUUUUGUUUCUUUAGUCACUUAACCCUGAUUGUAAUACCUUAUGGUGGAAGCUGUUAUGUUAAUGUUCUUGGGCAUCUUAGCUUUUUGUUUACAUUUAAAAAAUGUGUAUUGUAAAAUUAUGAGUCACUUGGUGGGGGAGGCAUGUCAAAUGUGACAGCAGAACUAAUGUGGAAGGAUAGAUUUAUGGCAAAACUCUCUGCCUUUUGGAGCACUAUCAGCUUGUCCAUGUGCACUAUUAGCUUUUGUUUCUCCAACACUUGUGGAUGCUUUUGUGAAUGCUGUCAGUCAGAUGUCUGGAAAAUUUUAAACAAGAACCACCAACUAAAGAAUUGUUUUGAGAGUUGAUUCAGAUCUUUUUGGCAGUGAGACAGUGAACAUGAAGUCACUGCCAGUUUUUGGUCUUUGUGGACCUUUUCCUUUCUUAUGUCUGACAGCUCAGGGCGGCAUUUUACUAUUGACUCUUAAUGGACCUGCAGUGCUAUAGCUGAGUCUGCACAGUUCAAAAUGCAAGGUUGGCAGUCUAGAAAGAUUGGGUAAAGAAGCAGCUUUGAGAGGAGUUCCUGCCCCAAAUUACUUGCUAAAAAUAUGUUAGAACUGAUAUAGCAUAAAACUGAUACAGCAUAAAAGGAUUAUUUGGAUAGAAGUGUUAUUUGGCUUAACAGGUCAGGAGGCAACAUAAUUUUUGCAGUGACUUCUGUUUCUUGAGGAGUUGCCAGGCAAGAAAUAUGAUAAGGAUUUUGAAGAAACUACUAUAGAGGUGGAGUUUCAUAGCUGUUUAUUUUUAUUCCAGAUUUUUCAUUUUUUUCUCUAUAAUCUCUUAAAAUGGUCUGAGAUUAGCACUUUUCACAGUUGUUGAAUCUUCUGAACUAUCAUGUUGGAAACAUUGGAUGUGCUCUUCUAUCUAGGGAAAAAUGUAGCCUUCAUUUUUGCCACAUGUGUUGCCAGACCGGACAUCAUAUGAAAGUUGCAAAAAAAAAAAUUCUGAAAAUCCAGCCUCACUUAGAAGUGAGGCAAUAUUUUCAUCUCUUUAUAAAGCUAUUUGUGAUUGCGUUCUUCACCAACAAUUUUUUUUUGCUGGAGGGGUGGUGGUAGGGGCAGUUUGCCACAAAGCUGAAGAAACGCAUUCUGUCACCAAAAAAUACCAUUUACAUUUUUUCUCCCUUUACAGAUUUCUUCUUUUUCUGGAAAAAAGUUUAACAUUUAAAUGAAAAUUUCAUUUGCCUUUUUAGUAUUAACGUGCCGUGAUAUUUAGUCUAACAACUUGUCCCUGAAUAUCUCUGUUGCUGUAACACUUUACCACCUUCAAGACAGCAAAGGAGGUGUGUUUUAAGUGCUAUGCCACUGGUUUUCAAUCCUUGACCUCAGAGGAAAAAAUAAUUCUACAUUAUGUUUUAUGACAGCUUCUCUGUAUGUUUUUUGUAAAGUUAAAUAUUCUAGACAAAGUCAGGUAUUAUCCAUAAGAUAUCAAACAAUUGGGAGAACUUUACCUGCUUGGUUAUAUUUAUUUCCUCUUUUAUAACCAGGGAAACACAAUUACCACCUCUUUUUUAGAGAUGAUGAAAGUGCUUAGAAAUAAAGCUCCAGCACCCUUAAAUGCCUGAGCUCCACCUAUUCUACAAGGCUGUGGGGACUCUUUGGCAUCCUCUGUGUUGCAUCUUUUCACUGAAACUUUAAUUUGAAUAUUUGAUUUUUCACCAAAUGUAUUUUCUUUAUUUUUUCCAUUGUUAGGAUAAUUACCCUUAGAAUUCUGUAGCUUCUGGAGAUAUUUACAAAUAUAUAUCUGUUAAUCUUUCCUUAACUCUAUGCCUAGUGCUAGUAUUUAAGGACAUGGGAGCUUAGGGGCUACUUAAUAAUUAAUGCCUUAUUCAAUUAAAAAAUUUUAACCUGUGUUUUCCUGACUUUAAAAAAAUACAUGUUUAUCAUGGAAUAUUUUAGAAUAAUAUAGAAUAUUGCUUCAUUCCCAAAUCAUCAGUGUGUGUGGUAUAUUCAUGUUUUUCAUUUAAUCAUCACUGUAACAGCUAGAUGAAUAACAGUAGGUCUCGUUUGACAUUACAGUGAAAGUUGAAGUUUUCAGAUCUCUUGCCUUGAAUUUUGUACCAAUUUUAUUUUAUUAAAGGCAGAAUAUUAAAUAUCUGUUUAAAAUACAAUGGAAAAAAUCAGCCAAGAGAAGUUUAAUGCCAUGUAUUUAAAAUAAUUCUUGCCAGUUCAAUUGCGAAAGUUCUCUGCUCAGUUUUGUGGUUAAAUGAUUAGGUCUUUCCAGUGGGGAAGGGCAGAAGGACUGAAAAGAAAGGGAAAUGUAAAAUUGAGGUGACUUUAGGGGAAAUGUUGGGAAUAGAAAAUUUCCAUGGAGUUCAUUUAGUGCUUCAAACACCUGUGCUCUGCUAAGGCAGGUAGAGAACUCUGUAUUGUGUGCAAAUCACUGACCUCGCUAAAAUUCCAGUUUCUUCUCUGCAAAAUGAGGAGUAAAUAAUAGUAUUCAUUCCAGCAGGUUUACUGUGGAGACUAAAUGAAAGAAUGAGUAUUAAAUGCUUUGUACCAUGACUAAGCACAUUAGAAUCAUUCAAAAAGUGUUAUUUAUUUUCUGUCAUUGACUCUCCAGAGGUGUGCAAAGCUAAAGUGACCCUGGCAUCUUUACUCUUUUUCCUCCCAUCUUCUAGUUCCUUGCUAUUACAAGCAUAGUCUAUGGGUUUGCAAUGUCAGCAUCACCAACAAUAUGGGGAGCUUGUUAGAAAUACAGAUGCUUAGGCCUCAUGCCAGACUUCACUUUUUCAGAAUCUGUGUUUUAAUAAGAUCCCCAGGUGAUCUGUACAUUGAAGCAUUGUUUGUACUCAUUUCUUGGAAAAAACAAUGUAAAAGACAUGGGCAGUAGAGAAAUAUAUCCUUUUGCUUUUGCUUUCUUUUCUAAGAUCUCACAAAUUUGUAGCUUUGGAUGAUGAUGGGAUGUGGAGUCUAUUCUAUUAACAUGUAUAUUGCUGCUAUUAUUACCGUUAUUAUCAUAGCAUUAUAUUUGCUGCUAUAUUAACAUAGCAUAAUAUUAAUGGAAGUGGAUUAUCCUGAAAUUGUCAGAAGUGUGGUUCAAAGCUUCUAUAUGCAUAUUGAUUUUCACCUACUUGUUGUAUCAGUUAUUGAGAAAGGGGUAUUAAUAUCUCUGAGUGUAAUAUAUUUGUGGAUUUAUCUAUUUCUCUUCACAGUUUUGUCUUCUUAUAUUUUGAAAUUCCAUUUUUAGAUGCACAAAGUUUGAGAUUAUUAUCUUCUCCUAAUGAAUUCACCCCUUUAUCAUUAUGAAAUUACCUUGUUUAUUCCUGGUAAUAUUCUUUGCCCUAAAAUCUACAUUACCUAAAGUUUAUUGACCUACUCUAGCUUCUGAUCAGUGUUAUUAUAGUGUAUCUUUUUAUAUGCUAUAACUUUUAAACUAAUUGUGCCUUUGUAUUUAAUGUGCAUUUUUUAUAGCCAGAUCAUACAUGGUUCUUGCUUUUUAUUCCAAUCUGACAUCUAUACUUUUAAUUUGGAUAUUUAGAACACUUACAUUUUAUUUGAUUCUUGAUACAGUUAGGUUUGAGUUUGUUUUAGUUUGUUCCAUUUGACCUUUGUUCCUCUUUUCCUUUUUUUCUGUGUUCUUUUGGAUCAAUUGAAUAUUUAAAAUUUUCUAUUUUAUCUCUUUUGUUGGCUUAUUAGCUAUGGCUCUGUUCUGUAUUUAGUGGUUGCUGUAAGGCGUAUCUAUACACCUUUAACAAAUCAAUUAACCUUCCAGUGAUGGCUUAUACUACUUUAGCUACUUUAUGAUAGUAUAAUACUAUUUUUCUCUUUCUGAUCAUUGUGCUAUUAUCAAGAUACAUUUUAAUUUUAUACCCGUAUUUUAUUUUUAUUUUUGUUAAAUAAUUAUCUUGUAAGGAGAUAUUUAUUUAUUUAUUUAUUUAUUUAUUUAUUUAUUUAUUUAUUUAUUGAGACGGAGUCUUGCUCUGUUGACCAGGCUGGAGUGCAGUGGCAUGAUCUUGGCUCACUGCAACCUCCGCCUCCCGGAUUCAAGUGAUUUUCCUGCUUCAGCCUCCCAAAUAGCUGGGACUAGAGGCAUACACCACCAUGGCAUGGCUAAGUUUUAUGUUUUUAGUAGAGAUGAGUUUCAUCGUGUUGGCCAGGCUGGUCUUGAAUUCCUGACCUCAAGUGAUUUGCCUGCUUCGGUCUCCUGAAGUGCUGGGAUUACAGGCGUGACCCACCAUGCCUGGCCUUGUAAGGAUAUUUAAAUAAGGAAAAUAAAUUUACUUCCUGUGCUCUGCAUGACUUUGUAUAGUCCACAUUUUUGUUAUUCCUUCUGUCUGGCAGACUUUCAUUAAUAGUUAUUGUAGCUAUGAAUUCAUUGCUUUUGAAUUUACAAAAACGUCUUUAUUUUGCAAGUUGUACUUUUCUGUUCAAUUUUUAAAAAAAUGUUGCUCCACUGUCAUUAUACUGUCAUUUCUACCAAUGAACUGAGUUACCCUUUGUUCUACUGACCACCUUCCUUUUUGCCUCCAGAUACAGCCCAUCCACUGUCUUCCAUAUCUGGAAAUUAUUGGGCAACAUCUCAUAGUGCUGACAAGUGCUCACAUUAUCAUGAUGGCAGAUGGAGAUUGAUGACCAGAGUGUUAAGUUGGCAGCUAAACAUGAGCUCAGAUUGAUGUCUUCAAUGCCAAUUAAUUUAGACAUGGAUUAUUUUAGCUUUCUUGCCUUUCUUGUCUGUAACUUCUCAUUCAGUGAGAACCCUGCCUCCCAACUUCUGCCAUCUAUUUAAUUGCUCAGUGCCAGUAUAGGUUUAUAGUGAUUUUAGAAUUAUUAACUCAUAUUUACAUGGGAAACAACUUAUAAACUACAGUGCUAAUGUAUACUUCCUUCUACCUUUAGUCUUACUAUCACCAUUCACUUUUUAAAGUUAACUUAGGUCAACAGCUUUCCUCCCCUCUUUCAAUGAGGUUAUUACAUACAUUUGUAAUAUAGCUAGUAGUUUGUAUUCCACCUUAGAAUCCUCCAAUCUCCUAAAUGAUUUUUAAAAUAUUUUCCUACACUAAGAUUCACUUUUUUGCAGCAAAAUUGUGUUUUAACAAAUACAAAGUGUUAUGUAUUCACCAUACAGUAUCAUACAGAACUAAUCUACCACCUUACAAUAUAUUCUAUGCUUCACCUAUUUAACUCUGCCUUCUCCCCAAGCCUCAGUCAACUUCUGAUUUAUUUGGAAUCUGUAUAGUUUUUGCCUUUUGCAGAAUGCUAUAUAAGUGGAAUCAUGCAGUAUUUAGCCUUUUCAGACUGGCUUUUUAAACUUAGCAAUAUGCAUUUAAAAUUCGUCUAUAUUUUUUCAUUGCCUAAUAUUUCAUUUGUUUUUAAGAGUGAAUAAUAGUCCAUUAUAUGGAUAUACCAUAGUUUGCUAUUCUACUUUUAUUAAUUUUUAAUUUUUGUGGUACAUUAGUAGAUAUAUAUAUUUAUGGGGUACAUGAGAUAUUUUGAUAUAAGCAUGCAGUGUGUAAUAAUAAUGCACUCAUUUAUUAAAGCACAUCUUGGUUGCUUUUGGCUUUUGGUAAUUAUGAAAGAGCUACUGUAAACAUUCAUGUGCAAGUUUUUGUGUGGACAUAAGUUUUCCAAUCAGUUAGGUAAAUACCUAGGAGCAUGAUAGCAGAAGUGUGUGGUAACACUGUGUUUAGCUUUGUAAGAUGCUGUAAAAUUUUGAUUGAGAUUGUGUUGAAUAUAUAUAUCAAUUAGGGAGAAUUGGAUUUAAUAUUGAACUUUGCAAUUCAUGAAUGUGGUACAUCUCUCAAGUUAUUUAGAUGUAAGAAGUUUCUUCUGUGAGUGUUUUGUAGUUUUCUGCUUGCAGACCGUACGUCUGUUGUCAUAUUUUAUCUACUUUUCUUUGUAUUUUUUGAAGAUUUCAGACCCCAAAUUUUCAUUCCUGGUAUAAAGGAAUAAAGUUGACUUUUCUAUGUUGAUCUUGUGUCCAAUGACUGCUAAAGUCACUUUUUAGUUUUAUGAGGUUUUUUUUGUAGAUUCUUUGCAGUUUUUAUGUGAGCAAUUGUGUUAUCUGUAAAUAAGGACAGUUUCAUCUUUUCCUUUCUAAUCUGUAUGCUUUUUAUUUCUUUUUCUUGCCUUGUUGCACUAACUAGAAUUUCCAGUACAAUGUUGAGUAAAAGCUGUGGUAAAGGGCAUCCUCUUCUUGUUCUGGAUCUUAGUGGAAAAGCAAAUUACUCUCUUACCAUUAAGUAUGAUUUUUAGCUAUAAGUUUAACAUAGAUACCUUUAUUUAGAUUAAGGAAGUUCUUUUCUAUUCCUAGUGUGCUGAUACUUUUUGGUUACAAGUGGAUGUUGAAUUUUCUUGAAAGCUUUUUUUGUGUAAAUUGAUCUGAUCAUAUAGUUUUGCUGAUGAUUAAUUUUUGAAUAUUAACCAGCUUUGCAUUUCUGGGCUGAAGCCCACUUGAUAUUGAAAUGUUAUCCUUUUAUGUGUUACUGGAUUUUAUUAGUUAAUAUAUUGUUAAGAAUUUUUGCUUAAUGAGAGACAGUCAUUAGUUUUCUUGGAAUGACUUCAUCUAGUUUUGUAGCAUCAUAGUGCUGGCCUGAAGGAAUGAGUUGUGAAGCAUUUCCCCCUCUUCAAUUUCCUGCAAGAGUUUGUAUAGAAUGAGUUUAAUCUUUUCUCUUAAAUUCGUGUUAAAAUUUACUAAGAAACUCUCUGAGCCUGGAGUGAGUUUUUUCCCCUUUCUAAUGGAAGCAUUUUUAACUACAAAUUCGAUUUCUUACAGGCCUUGUAUGGAUUUAAUCCAUAUGGAACCACUCAGAUUACCCAAUUUUUCUUGAGUAAGCUUUGGUAGUUUGUCUUUCAAGGAAUUUUUAAAAUUUUAUCAUUGUCUUUAUUUAUAUGUCUCAAGUUGGAGUAAUACAGGAAUUUAAGAAUUAACUGAAUUGGCUCGUUAAAUUAUAUCAGUUUUAACUAACUUGCAAUAAAAACAGCAAAUUUCUUUCUAACUUAAAAAAGGAAUGCAUAAAACUUAGUUGUUUUCUUCUUAUGGAGGAGUUGCUGUUUGUCAUUUCUUAAGCUUUGUGUCCUGUAGUUGACUAGAGGGAGACAUUGUUCUUAAGACGCUAAAGUAAUUUAUUUUUAUUUAUUUUAGCAACUUACAGACAAUUCAGCUAUCUGGAACAUAUAAAAUUUUUUUUGUUUUCAUGACUGGGUCUUGCUUUGUCACCUAGACUGGAGUGCAGUGGCACAAUCAUAGCUCACUGCAACUCUAGCUCACUCGCUCAAGCAAUCCUCUCGCCUCAGCCUCCCAAGUAGAUAGGACUACAGUUGCGUGUCACCACACCUGGCUAAUUUAAAUUUUUGUGUGUGUGGAAAGAAAGGUCUCACUGUGUUGCCCAGGCUGAUUGAACUUUUGAGCUCAAGCAGUAUCCCCUUCGGCCUCUCAACGUGCUGGGAUUAUGGGUGUGAGCUACCGCACCUGGCCCAUGAAGAUUUUUAAUAGCUAAUUAUUACCAUGUUAUUGCAAACUAACUUGGGAGACUGUGUGACCAGUGUGAAUAUAUUUAUCUAGGAUUGCAGAGCAGAAUUUGCAGCUGUGUGAAUCCAGAAUAUAUAUUACCUAUUAUUUGUAUACAAACAUAAAAUUGUGAAUUAUUUACAAUAAAUUAUGUUAAUUGAGCAGUUCUCCCCCUUUUUAUAAUGUACAGCAUUAUGAAAUGAACAUUAUUUAUAAUUUAAGUUCACAGAAGAAUCCCUGUUUUCAAAGCCAAAUUGGAGUAAGCUUUCUUAUCCUAGGCUUACUUAGUAGUGCCAGAAUUGAAUCAGAGUCUAUGUGGUACAUUUGGUCCCAGUUCUUUUUCUGCUUCCUAUAUCAAAUUUUCCACAUGGCUUUGAAGAUUCAUAUAUUUACCCUUCUGUUGACUUUGAGUAUAACUUACUCUGACCAAAUAGAAUAAAGCUGAAGUGAUAGCUAAUAUGCUUUUUUUUAUUAUUAUACUUCAAGUUCUAGGGUAUAUGUGCACAAUGUGCAGGUUUGUUACAUAUGUAUACAUGUGCCAUGUUGAUGUGCUGCACCCAUUAACUCGUCAUUUACAUUAGGUAUAUCUCCUAAUGCUAUCCCUCCCGCCUCCCCCCACCCCACGACAGGCCCCGUUGUGUGAUGUUCCCCUUCUUGUGUCCACGUGUUCUCAUUGUUCAAUUCCCACCUAUGAAUGAGAACAUGUGGUGUUUGGUUUUUUUGUCCCUGCGAUAGUUUGCUGAGAAUGAUGGUUUCCAGCUUCAUCCAUGUCCCUACAAAGGACAUGAACUCAUCCUUUUUUAUGGCUGCAUAGUAUUCCAUGGGUGUGUAUGUGCUGCAUUUUCUUAAUCCAGUCUAUCAUUGUUGGACAUUUGGGUUGGUUCCAAGUCUUUGCUAUUGUGAAUAGUGCCACAGUAAACAUAUGUGUGCAUGUGUCUUUAUAGCAGCAUGAUUUAUAAUCCUUUGGGUAUAUACCCAGUAAUGGGUUGGCAGGGUCAAAUGAUAUUUCUAGUUCUAGAUCCUUGAGGAAUCGCCACACUGUGUUCCACAAUGGUUGAACCAGUUUACAGUCCCACCAACAGUGUAAAAGUGUUCCUAUUUCUUCACAUACUCUCCAGCACCUGUUGUUUCCUGACUUUAAUGAUCGCCAUUCUAACUGGUGUGAGAUGGUAUCUUGUUGUGGCUUUGAUUUGCAUUUCUCUGAUGGCUAGUGAUGAUGAGCAUUUUUUCAUGUGUCUGUUGGCUGCAUAAAUGUCUUCUUUUGAGAAGUGUCUGUUCAUAUCCUUCACCCACUUUUUGAUGGGGUUGUUUUUUUUGUGUAAAUUUGUUUGAGUUCUUUGUAGAUUCUGGAUAUUAGCCCUUCGUCAGAUGAGUAGAUUGCAGAAAUUUUCUGUAGGUUGCCUGUUCACUCUGAUGGUAGUUUCUUUUGCUGUGCAGAAGCUCCUUAGUUUAAUUAGAUCCCAUUUGUCAAUUUUGGCUUUUGUUGCCGUUGCUUUUGGUGUUUUCGACAUGAAGUCCUUGCCCAUGCCUAUGUCCUGAAUGGUAUUGCCUAGGUUUUCUUCUAGGGUUUUUAUGGUUUUAGGUCUAACAUUUAAGUCUUUAAUCCAUCUUGAAUUAAUUUUUGUAUAAAGUGUAAGGAAGGGAUCCAGUUUCAGCUUUCUACAUAUGGCUAGCCAGUUUUCCCAGCAUCAUUUAUUAAAUAGGGAAUCCUUUCCCCAUUUCUUGUUUUUUUCAGGUUUGUCAAAGAUCAGAUAGUUGUAGAUGUGUGGUAUUAUUUCUGAGGCCUCUGUUCUGUUCCAUUGGUCUAUAUUUCUGUUUUGGUACCAGUACCAUGCUGUUUGGGUUACUGUGGCCUUAUAGUAUAGUUUGAAGUCAGGUAGCGUGAUGCCUCCAGCUUUGUUCUUUUUGCUUAAGAUUGUCUUGGCAAUGUGGGCUCUUUUUUUGGUUCCAUAUGAACUUUAAAGUAGUUUUUUCUAAUUCUGUGAAGAAAGUAAUUGGUAGCUUGUUGGGGAUGGCAUUAAAUCUGUAAAUCACCUUGGGCAGUAUGGCCAUUUUCAUGAUAUUGAUUCUUCCUAUCCAUGAGCAUGGAAUGUUCUUCUAUUUGUUUAUGUCCUCUUUUAUUUCGUUGAGCAGUGGUUUGUAGUUCUCCUUUUUAAACCUGUGCUUUAACAGGAGGCAUUGAGUGUUUCUGCUUGCCCUCUUGCUUUUCUGUCAUCGUCAUGAGAAAUAUACUCAGGAAAAGAAUGAAGAGUCUGAAACUAAUCCACCUCCUAGCUGCCCACUGUAGAUAUGUGCUAUAUAUUAUCAGUACCCCAAAGCUCCCCUUGUACCUCCUUUCAAUCACUACUACUCUCCAAUGGUGGCUUUCCUGACUGACGACCCACAGAUUACAUUUUACCCUCUUCCCUUUUGCAUCCUCCGUUUGGCAGAAAUUCUGAGGGAAAAUUAGCCUUAUGCUGGAGGCUGCCCAGAUCUACCAAAAGCCCUCUUAGUUUUAUAUACUAUCUUAUGAUGAAAAGAUAACUUUAUAAGACAGUAAACUAAUGCCUAGGUUUAGUUUAUAAAAAUUACUAGAAUCACCUUACAGUGAUUCCUAAGGUCUUGGCAUUUUUAGCCUGUUAUUCUACCUCUUCUAUGAGAAUACUCUAAUUAGGAAUUCGAAUUGUGACUAUGAAUUCUUGUUAGCCAUCAAAAGGCAUGACAUUCUUUACUCUAAAAUACUUAGCUUUCCGAGGCAGGAGAGAAUACUAAUGAGUGUUUAAAUAAAAACAGACCUUGGUUAUAUAUCAAUUAACCAGAUUUCUAUUUUCUCUUUAGGUUUAACUUUCUACUACCUCAGUGUAACCUUGUACAAAAGCAUUCCAUGUAGAGUACCUGCUUUUUUAAACUACUUUACUUUCUUACAGAGUAAGCCAUCUGCUUUCUAAAGCAUUGAGACAAGAAACACAGACUCAGUGAAAAACAUACUAUGAAGCCAUGUAGUAUAGUGCUGGAAAAAAGUACAAGACCUACUUAGAUUCAACGCAAGUAUAUAUUCCUUUUUAGCUGCAUGAACCUGAUCAAAUUACUUUUUAAAGCCACAAUUUAUCCCUUUAUGGUCUGUGGAUAUGUAACAGCUUCGACCUUAUACAGUUGAGAUUAUAUGCUGUAACAAAUGCAUGUAAAGGCUUAGCACAGUGCCUGGUGUGGCAUAAGCAGUCAGAAAGAGCUCCUUGACAUUAUCAUUAUUAUAAUUAUUACUGUUACUGUUAAAUAUUUUACUGGGAAUAGGAAAAUCUAAGCAAUUUUUGAAGGCUUUACUGAGUGAGAAAAAAAUACUUAUUCUUUCUCCAUAGUUCUAUACAUUUUAAAUUUUAAUAUUCUUUAGUUGAUUAUUGCUAAGACCUUGAAACACCCUUUUCCCCUUCAAAUCUCUGUUAAUCUUCAAGUUAAAAUUUUCUGUUUAUAUGCAUUCUUGAAAGUAUAUGUAUUCACUUCCUAUUACAGUAUCAAUUACCACAAAUUUAGUGGCCUAACACAAAAGAAAUUCUUAUCUUACAGUUCUGGAGGUCAGAAAUCCAAAAUCAAUCUCAAUGGGUUAAAAUCAAGGUGUCAGCAGGACUGUUACCCUUCUGGAGGCUCUAGGGAAGAAGUCUGUUUUGAAAAUUCCUUUCUGUCUCUUCUUCAGGCUGCCCAUAUUCCUUGGCUCCUGGCUCUGUAUCACUUCAACAUCUAACAUCAUCACAUCUCCUUUUCUGACUCUCUUUUUCUUCUCUAUUAUAAGGACUCCUGUAAUUACAUUGGGCUUACCCAGAUAAUCUUCUCAUUCCUAAUUUAAUCACAUCUGCAAAGUCCCUUUUGCCAAGUAAUGUAACAUAUUUGCAGGUUUUGGGGAUUAGGAUGUGGACAUCUGUGGGUGUACCGUUACUCCGCCUGCCUACCACAGUCUGCCUUCUGGCCCCCAGAGAUUUAUGUCUGUUCUACAUGCAAAAUAUAUUCACCCCAUCCCAACAUUCCCAAAGUCUAAUGCUGCAUUCCCAUUGCAGCAUCAUUUCAAAGUCCAAAAUCUCUUUUAAAUCUUAUCAGCUCAAAAGUUUCGAACCGUAUGAACUCAAUCAUCUAGAUUAGGCAUGGGUGAGAGUCUGAGAAUGAUCUUUCCUAAGGUACAGUUCCUAUCUAUCUGUGAAAUUCUGAAAUUCAGACAGGUUAUUUGCUCCCAAAAUGGUGGGGCAACGAUGGGAUAGCAAUUAUAAACAUUCCCGUUCAAAAAAGGAGAAAAUAGAAGGAGAAAUGGAGUUACCUGUUUUAGUCAAUUUCAUAAUCCAGCCUGGGAAAAACAUCCUCUGUGAUUUGAGGGUCCACACUUGUGGGCUCAGGGCUCUGCCCUUUAGAUCAUCCUUCCUUUUUCAUGAAAGGUGGCACAUGUUUGUGGCUGAGCAGUUUCAUCAGCCUGUUUCCUGCCUGUGGUAUUUUGGGAGUCUGAGAGUCUUUUUUGAAAUUUUGUUUAAAAUUUUGUCUUCUCUUUCCCCCUUUCAAUUUAAACUGGCAGUGUUUCUGUUUAUGUAAUGUUCUGAAGAACUUUUGGGGCCUAGUACAGUGGCUCAUGCCUGUAAUCCCAGUGCUUUGAGAAGCCAAGGUGGGAGGAUCACUUGAGGCCAGGAGUUUGAGACCAGCUUGAGCAACAUAGUAAGACCUUGUCUCUACAAAAAAAAAAAAAAAUUUUUUAAGAACCUUGUAGAUUUUCUGUGUAUGUUGGGGAUUCAUUUUUUUUUUGAUAAGAGGCUCUUCCAUAAAUCUUUCCUGGAUGUACAAAGGCAAUUACAACCUUACACACACACACACACACACACACACACACACACACACACACACUUAGAGGAAAGCAACUGCCUACACACACACACACACACACACACACUACUUAGAGGAAAGCAACUGCCUGCCCAACCUUGGACUAAUAGUCAUCCUUGUUAUUGAUCCUUGUAGCCAAGGAUUAUUGUCUCCAAACAAUUAUGUAAUCCUGCUCAUUUUCCCUUUAAAAAUCUUUUUUCCUUUACCUCUGUGAAUAUGCACAUAGUUUACAAUGGCAUGUGUAUUUCCAUUGCAAUGCCCUAUUCCCAAAUAAAUAUAAUUUUCUUUUAUUGAGCCUCUUUCUGUUACUUAAGUUGACAAAUGGUGUCAGAAGUGGAAUCUGAAGAAGGGUCACCAUCAGUGUUUUCCUGUGUUUUUACUGAGUUUUUGACCAUCAGUUGCUUGUGUGCUUUGUGAUUUUAUCUUUUGGAAUUUUUUGAGGCUUGUGAUUAAGGUAGGUUUAUCCAAAGUAGAUUUGAGUUUUUUUCAUGUACUUUGUGGAUGCUGUCAUGUGGUAAUCUCUGUAAUCUAGAUUGUCAUCUUGUACCAUCUAAGUGGUAUAAAUUUUACCUGAAAAUAUACAAGAAGGAAGGCUCAUAAUAACAAAUUCUUAGGGCGAUUUGUGUGGCCACUUUAGUUUUUCAUUUUCCUACCAUACUAUCUGUAAAUAUAAUACAGAUGGAGUGAAGAAAUGCAAGAAACAAAGCCUGCUCAGCUAAAUCUAUCUCUUUUUUGUGUGCCAUAGCAUAUAAACAUGUGUUCCAUAAGGGAAGGCGCUGUGAUAAGACAGCAGAAAAUCUUGGACCUGGUGGGAGAAGAGGAUUAGGUAUUAGCUUUAAGUUUUGAUUAUCUUAAUAAAAACCUCAAGGAAUUUUAUAAAACAAAAAUAAGAAAACCUCCCAGAAGUAAGUGAGUUUAAUAAUAUUACAGGAUCCAGGGCCGGGCGUGGUGGCUCAUGCCUGUAAUUCCAGCACUUUGGGAGGCUGAGGUGGGGGGAUCACAAGGUCAGGAGUUCAAGACCAGCUUGGCCAACAUGGUGAAAUCCCAUCUCUACUAAAAAUACAAACAUUAGCCAGGCGCAGUGGCGGGUGCCUGUAAUCCCAGCUACUUGGGAGGCUGAGGCAGGAGAAUUGCUUGAAACCAGAAGGCAGAGGUUGCAGUGAGCCGAGAUCAUGCCACUGCACUCCAGCCUGGGCAAAAGAGGGAAACUCUGUCUCAUUUAAAAAGUUAGAUAAAAAAAUAUAUAUAUUACAGGAUCUAAGAAAAACAUACAAAUAUCUAUCACAAGGAAAAAUUGGAAACUGAAAUUUUAAAAAUAGCACCAUUUAUGAUACUUUACCUCAAAAUGAAACAGGUAUUAAAUAUACAGAGAAUCUGUAUGCUGAAAGCUACAAAAUACUUAUGAAAGAAAUGAACAGAUUGACUACAUUCAUGGAGUAGAAGAUUCAACAUAGUGAAGAUGUUAAUUAUCCUGGAUUGGUAAGGAGAUCCCAAUCAAAAUCCUAGCAAGAUUCUUUGCAGCUAUUCACAAGAUGAUUCUAAAAUCUUUAUGGAAAGUUAAAGGAGCUAGAAUGCUAAAACACUUUUUUAAAAGAUGAAAAAAGUUAGAAAACUCACACUAACCAAUUGUAAGGCAUACUGUAACACUACAGUAAUCCAGUACAGUACUGGUGAAAGGACAGAUCCAUAGAUUAAUGGAGCAAAACUGAGAUUCCAGAACUGGACCCAUGCAAAUAUGGUCAGUGGUUUUGACAAAGUUGCAGUGGUGACCUGGCUUAUGGAAUAUUUUCUGAUAUGAAACCAAAAGUAUGAUACAUAAAAGAAAAAACAUGAUUAAUUGGAUUUUAGUUUUAUCUUUGAAAGAUACUGUUAAAGAGAAUGGGGAAAAAAACUAUUCUCCCGUAGGUUGGGGAAAAAGAAUUUUGCAAAUUAAUAUCCAGAGGUAUAUUCAGAAUAUCUAAAGAAGUCUGAAAACUCAACAAUAAGAAAACAAUCUAACAAAAAGGCAAAGGUUUUAAGUGACACUUCACCAAGGACAGCAUAGUACGGCAAUAAACACAUGAAAACAUGUCCAACAUCUUUACUCAUUAGGGAAAUGCAAAUGAAAACUACAAUGAGAUAGUAUUAUCUUACACACCUUCUAGAAUAGGUAAAGUAAAAAACAAUAUUGACAAUAUUAAAUACUGUCAGGGAUGCAGGGGAACUGAAAUUCUCAUAUGUUGCUCAUGGUAUACAUAUACAAAAUGGCAUGGCAUUUUAAUAAAACAUUUGGCAGUUUCUUAUAAAAGUUAAGCUUAUUUUUUGACUCAGCAAUCCCACUCCUAGGCAUUCAUCCUACAGAAAUGAAAAGUUAUGAUCACACAACAUACUCUAGAAACAUGUAUAUAGCAGCACUAUGCAUAAUUGCCAACAAUGAAAACAACUCAAAUGUCUUUCAGUGAGUGGGUGAAUACAAACAGGUAGAGCCACUGUUUCUGAUAAGUGUGUCCCAUUAGAAUUUAUCACAUCAUUUUUCACUCAUGUGUAAUGUGUUGUCUUUUCAAUGUAUGUUUCUAAAUGUAGUUUUGUUUUCUUUGUGAGGUUCACUGAGCUUUUUGAACAUAAACAUUUAUAUCUUUCAACUAUUUGGGGUAAUUUCAGCCAUUAUUUCUUGCAGUAUAUUUUCCAACUUUUUAUUUUGCUUUUCUCACACUGGGAUUCCAAUUUAUAUAUAUAUGUACCUGCUAAUAUUGUUGCAAAAUUCAUUGAAUCUGUUUAUUUUUAAAAUCCUUUGUCUUUCUGUUUCUUAGAUUAGAUGAUGCAUAUUGAUCUGUCUUAAAGCUCACUGACUCAAUCUUCUGACAUCUCCAGUUUUCUUUUUAGAAGCUUUUUCAGUGAAAUUUUUCAUUUCAGAUAUUGAAUUUUUCGAUUUAAAAGUAUCCAUUUUGUUAUUUUUAUAGUUUUUCUUUUUCUGUUCAGAUUUUCUUCAUCUGUUUAUUCUUUAUGAAUAUAAUUAUAGUAGCUACUUUUAAUCUCUUUUAGAUAACUCCAAAAUCUGGGUCAUUUUUGUUGUUGUUUUUUAUUUUUUAAAUGCUGCUACCAUUUACUGAUCACUUGUACCAGUCAUUGUCCUAAGCAAUUUAUAGAAAUAAACCCAUUUAAUCCUUACAUGUGGGUCAGGAGCUAUUAUCAUCUCCAUCGUACAGAUAAGUAAGGAGGCACAGAGAGGAAAAUUCUUUCCUGACAGCAGUUAAUGAAUGUGGUUUCUUACGUAUUUGUUAAAACAGCUGCCAUUUUUUAUUUGUUUGUUUGUUUAGAGACAGAGUCUCGCUAUGUUGCCCUUGCUGGCCUUAAAUUCCUGGGCUCAAGUAAUCCUCCCACCUCAACCUCUCAAGUAGCUGAGACUAUAGGCAUCUGCCACUGUACCCAGCUCACUUCAUUUUUUUUUUUUUUUAAAGAAAAGUGAUGGAGUCAAAAGGUCCACUAUUAAAAACAAAACAAAACAAAAUUCCCUAGGUUAAAAAAGCAAAAACAAAAAAAAUCUUAGCAUCAGAGUCCACUGGGUUAAAAAUAAUGAGAAUAAAAAAUCCCUGCUCAUAACAUCCUCCUUCUAGAAUGGUUGGAAGGUCAGAGCAUUUUUAUAACAAAGUCUUUCAUUUCCAUUGAUUUCCUUCAUGGGUCAUGUUUUCUUGUAAUUUGGAAUAUCUCCUCCAUAUUAUGAAUGACAUAUUGUAGACAGUUUAUAUUCUGUUGUAGUCCUCUGAAGAGGUUUUUUUUGUUUUGUUUUGUCUUGUUUGUUAAGAGGCAGGGUCUUGCUAUGUCACCCUGGCAGCUCAAGCAAUCCUCCUUCCCCAGCUUCCCAAGUAUCUGGGACUACAGCUGUGUGCCACCACACCCAGCUACUUAAAAUUUUUUUUCUUUUUAGAGAUGGGGUCUCACUAUGUUGCUCAGGUCGGUCUUGAACUUGUGGCCUCAGACAAUCCUCCUGCCUCAGUCUCCUGAGUAGCUGUGAUUAUAGGCUCAAACCACAGUGUCAGGCCUCUGAAGAGUUUUGAACUUUGUUUUGUUUUGCCUGAAUUCAAACUCCAAACUCUUGUUUUCUGAAAUUGGGCAGUAGCUGAAAUUUUUUAUUAGUUCAUUUAGUCCUAACUGAGCUGCCUGGAGACUUCUCUGUGUAUGUAUAUGCCAGACAGAGAUUUAGACAGAAUUUAAUAUAUAGGAUUUGUGCAGUUCCUUUCUCCUUCCUUCAAUAUCCCACCUCAGUUUCCAUCUGACAUUGUCAUCCUUAACUCUGUUUUCUGAUUUAACAACAGAUAAGACUGUUUUUAUCUGAGAUUUAGCCUUUCUGCUCAGGAUUGACUGAGGCCUACACUCAGGCAAAAAGUCAUAAGAAUGAAAAAUUCACCCACUGUCAGUCCCUUCUAGUUGGCACCUCCCCUCCCAUUUUUCCUGUUUCUGGCUCAUCUCCAGCGAUUUUAGACAGUUGUGUGUUUUUUUUUGUUUUUGUUUUUUUUAAGAGUUUUUAUGUCUAGAGCUCUAAGUUGUUUUCUAUGGGAGGAUUGGUUCAAAUAUUGUGAGACGACUUCAUCAUUACAGGAAGUUGGACUCCUGUUAUUUUUCUUUUGAUUUGUGUCAUAUCUGUAGUAACACAUCCUCUUUUUGCCUUAUAUUGGUAAUAAAUAUUCCCCCCCUUUUUUGUAUCCAAUCAGUCUCUGAUUUUUCCCCUUUUCCAUCAGUCUUGCAGAGUAUUAUCAGUUUUAUUUAUAUUCAAAAAGCCUUCUUUUGACGUUCUUACUUUUCCUUCAUGUUUGUUUUUUAUUUUCUUGAUAUCUGCUCUAGUAUUUAUUUCCUUCCUUCCAUUUACUUUGGGCUUAAUUUGCUCAUCUUUUUCUAGCAACUUAAGAUGCAAAUGAAGAUCAUUGUUUUUAAGCCUUUUUUUUUUUUUUUUUGAGACGGAGUCUUGCUGUGUCGGCCAGGCUAGAGUGCAGUGGUGCAAUCUUGGCUCACUGCAACCUCCGCCUCUUGGGUUCAAGCAGUUCUCCUGCCUCAGCCUCCCAAGUAGCUGUGAUUACAGGUGCGCACCACCAUGCCUGGCUAACUGUUUUGUAUUUUUAGUAGAGACGGGGUUUCACCAUGUGGGCCAGGCUGGUUUUGAACUCCUGACCUCAAGUGAUCCUCCUGCCUUGGCCUCCCAAAGUGCUGGGAUUACAUGCGUGAGCCACUGCGCCCGGCCUUUCUAUAUUUUUAAUAAGCAUUUGAAGAUAUAAAUAUCCAUUUAAGCUUUGCUUUAGCUGUAUCUCACAAAUUAUGAAGUACUAUAUUUGCAUUAUCAUUCAGUUUAAAUUAUUUUAACAUAAUUUAUUCCUUCUUUGAUAUGAGUUAUUCUGAAGUAUAUUGUUACUGAUUUUUUACUGUUAUUAACAUUUCUUUGUGUUUAGAUACUCUGUAUAAUUUUAGCCUUUUAAAAUUUAGUGAAACUUGUGUUAUGGCCCAGUAUGUAGUGUAUCUUGAUGAAUAUUCUCUGUGCACUUGAAAAUAAUGUAUAUUUUACAGCUGUUGGGGUAGGGCUUUCUAAAUUUAAUUGUCAGUUGCAUUAAGGUACUUGAUAGUGUCAUUUGAAACAAUGUUACUAGGGUUUUAUUCCUUUAUUAUUAUUAUACAUAUAUGAUCUAUUUUAUCAUCAUGAAAUUUUCCUCCAUACUUGUUAAUACUUCUCAUGAAAUCCAUUUUGUUUGAUAGUAAUAUGGUCACAAAACUCUCUUAUGGUUAUUGUUUGUACAGUAUGUCUAGUUUCAUUCUCUAUACUUGCAACUUGUCUGUUUUAUUUUCAGUGUAUCUCUUAUAGACAGCAUAUAGUUACAUCUUGCUGUAUGUAUGUGUGUGUGUAUUUUAUGGGGGUUGGUCUUGCUUUUUUAUACAGUCUAACAAUUCCUGCCUUGUGAUCAUGAGUUCUUAGUCUGUUAUACUUAAGUACCACAUUUUCUUUAUCCAGUCCACUGUUGAUUCCAUGUCUUUGCUACUGUGAAUAGUGUUGCGAGGAACAUAGAGUGUUGCAAGUACAUGUCUUUUUGUUAGAACGAUUUAUUUUCUUUUGGGUAUAUACCCAGUAAUGGGAUUGCUGGGUCGAGUGGUAGUUCUUUACUUUAAGUUCUUUGAUAAAUCUCCAAACUGCUUUCCACAGUGGCUGAACUAAUUUACAUUCCCACCAGCAGUGUAUAAGCAUUCCCUUUUCUCCACAACCUCACCAACAUCUUUUAUUUUUUAUUUUUAUUGAUAGCCAUUCUGACUAGAGUGAAAUGAUACCUCAUGGUUUUGAUUUGCAUUUCUCUAAUGAUUAGUGAUGUUGAACUUUUUAAAAUAUAUUUGUUGGCUGCAUCUUUGUUUUCCUUUGAGAAGUGUCUGUUCAUGUCCUUUGCCCAUUUUUAAAAAUGGGGUUAUUUGGCUUUUGCUUGUUUAACUUCUUAAGUUCCUUAUAGAUUCUAGAUAUUAGACCUUUGUUAGAUGCACAGUUUAUGAAUAUCUUCACCCGUUCUGUAGGUUAUUUAUUUACUCUGUUGAUAGUUUCUUUUGCUGGGCAGUGGUCCCACUUGUCAAUUUUUGUUUUUGUUGCAGUUGCUUGUAGGAACUCGGUCAUAAUUUUUAUGCCAACGCCAAUAUCCAGAAUGGUAUUUCCUAGGUUUUUAUCUAGGAUUUUUAUAGUUUGAGAUCUUAUAAGUCUUUAAUCCAUCUUGAGUUAAUUUUUGUAUAUGGUAGAAGGCAGGGGCCUAGGUUCAUUCUCCUGCAUGUGGCUAGGCAGUUAUCCCAACACCAUUUAUUGAAUAGAGAGUCCUUUCCCCAUUGCUUAUUAUUGUCAACAUUGUGGAAGAUUAGAGGUUGUAAGUGUACAGCUUUAUUUCUGUGUUCUCUAUCCAGUUCCAUUGGUCUAUGUGUCUUUUUUUUUGUGCCAGUACUGUGCCAUUUUGGUUACUAUAGCCUUGUAGUAUAGUUUGAAGUCAGGUAGUGUGAUGCCUCUGGUUUUGCUCUUUUUGCUUAGGAUUGCAAAGUUUAGUCUUUGUUCACACAAUCAUUUGGAAUCAAUGUGGGUCUUGCAUUAAAGCUUUAUUAGAAUGUGUCCAGGUCAACCUUUAUCCUGGGGCUAAUUUAGCCCCAUUUCUAAGAUAUGGCCUCUCUGAGGACCCUAUCAAAUAUCUUGUGUAUUACAUAGUUUUUGUACUCUGGCUGAUGACAGUGCUACCUGGUUUUGACCCUGUGUGAACUCUGGCAGUUGUUCAGCCUUCUGCUUUCCAGUGUUUUUUUUCAUUGGCCACAGGUGUUUCAUUCCAUAAGUAUAUGGAUUAAUACUCAGCCAAAGAUGAGAGCAUCCCUUUGCAGACCCUCAGAGCUCUCUGUGCAGCUUUCCCCUCUCUAGUACUCUGCCCUGUGAAGUCUAGCUAGCAUCCUUAGCUUCCAUGCAUGCCAGUCUCUCUGCGUAACUCAGCAAGACCACCAGGUUCCGUUAGUAUUUCCUUUCACUGUGCUGUGGCCUGGCAACUGCCUUUAGGCAACAAGCUGGGAUGAUCGAGUCACCCAAUUUUUUUACCUUUUCUCUGGCAGCAUAUCCUCCUCUGUCCUUUCUCCAACAUCUGGAACUGUUGUUUCAUACAUUUUUUUUUCAUUUUUCUAGUUGUUUAUAGCAUGAGGACAAUUCUUGUCCCAAUUUAUUCAUCUUGGGUGGAAGCAGAAGCUCCUGAAAAGACAGUAUUUAUGGUCAUCAUUACCAGAGGGUUAUUUUUUUUUUUUUGUAGGUCAGGUUGAAUGAAAUUCUAGAUAUAUUUUUACUUUAAGCCAUCUUUGAUUUUAAAUUUCAUAAAUUAACAACAGAAGAUGAAUUAGAGAAGAAAAAUAGCCUAUAAAAUUAGGAGUUAUACUUUUCUUUACUUAUUAUUUGUUUGUUUGUUUUUGAGAUGGAGUCUCGCUUUGUCACCCAGGCUGGAAUGCAGUGGCGUCAUAUCGGCUCACUGUAAGCUCCACCUCCCGGGUUCACGCCAUUCCUCUGCCUCAGCCUCCCAAGUAGCUGGGACUACAGGCGCCCACCACCACACCGAGCUAAUUUUUUUGUAUUUUUAGUAGAGACGGGGUUUCACUGUGUUAGCCAGGAUGGUCUCGAUCACCUGACCUCGUGAUCCACCCACCUCAGCCUCCCAAAGUGCUGGGAAUACAGGCGUGAGCCACUGUGCCCGGCCUUUUCUUUACAUUUUUAACAGACAUCCAACUUACAGAUUUACUAUGACUUGUGUGGUUCAUUCUCUUCACUAUCAGAAUCUUCCAAGAUUCAUAUCAGUUACUGAAUUUUGUCAAGCUCCCUAGUUAUGGUUGUGUUUUAUUCUAAGAACCCACCCCUAGUACUUGCUUUCCCUUAUUCUCAUAUUUUAAAGUACUUAUUUCAGAAGUGGUUUGGGAAUUUUUGAAAAUAUUUUUUUUUUUGAGACAGAGUCUCGCUCUUGUCCCCCAGGCCAGAGUGCAAUGGCACGAUCGUGGCUCACUGCAACCUCCACCUCCCAGCUUCAAGCAAUUCUCCUGCCUCAGCCUCCAGAGAAUACUUUUUUUUUUUUUAAACAAAGACAACCUAUAUGUAGCUAGUCAAGUCAUGGCACUCCCUUUUAAUUUUCUCUUGAAGAUUACCUAGAUUUUAGCAGGAUAGGAAUAGCAUUUAAUACUAUUCUUAGGUUUUUCCAAGUAUUAAUGCCGUUGUCUUUGUUUGCUGUGUCUAGAAUGUAGUUGUCUCCCUCUUGACCACACAAUUCUUAAGUAGGUAGGCUCUGCCUUGUCUUCCUUUUAUUUUGUGUAUGGUUCCGUACUUGAACUUGAUUCAAACAUGUCUAUCCACCUUCCCCAAUACCAUCUCUCAGUUGGCAACUUGUUCUGGCUCUUUAACUGAAGCAUGUAGUUGAUAUGCUGAUUUUUUUCAAUAAUAGAUUUUAUAUUUGGGUAUUCCCACAUCAUCAUGGGAAAUUUUUUGAAGAAUCCAUCAUAUUAAACAUUCUUUCUGGUUCAGUUAUUGAAAAGUUUGUUUAUAUUUUGCCACAGGGGUUUGUGUGGUUUUAUUGUAGGAUGCUUUUUUUGUUGUUGAUUCUGAUUUACUUGGCUGGCCUAUGAAUGCCAUUCUGAAUUGGUUACUAAAAAUGUUUAUAUUUAGACCUGGACAGAUAAUUUUUUCUUUCGUUUUAUGAGUAGCUUUUUAAAAUAAAAAACUUUUUAACUCAACAGAAGUCUAAAGAAGGUGGAUCAUUUAGUAUUUAAUGGGGAACACAAGUGUUGAGGUAAUGAGUAUAUGAGAUAUUCGAGUUUCAUUUUUCAAGUUACUUAGGUUAGAAUUUUUUUUCGUAGUAGGGAUUAUUUGGGGGUCAUUUUACGUACUGCCUUGAGAAGAGUCUUGGUGCCUUUUGUUAUUAAAGUAUUGCAAUAGGUAAUGUUUGCAAGGUAUUACAAUAUAUUGAUACACUUUAAUAUUAUAUAUAGUAUUCCUCCAUGUCAAUAAGUAUUGAAGAUGUUUAUGAUUGAUUUUUUCCUUUAAUUUUUUCUUACUUUUCACUUCUUGACUUCAUACAUCAAAGAAGAAAUCCAGAGUGAAAUUAGAGAGUAUUUUGAACUAAAUGAAAAUGAAAACACAACACAACCUGCUAAAAUUACUUAGAUGUAUCUAAAGCAGUACUUAAAGGGAAAUUUUACCACUGAAAUCCUACAUUAGAAAAGAAGAAAGGUCCCAAAUCAGUAAAAUCAGCUUUCACCUUAAACUAGUAAAAGCAAAACAAAUGAAACCAGAAGUUUACAGGAUUAUAAUAAGGAUCAUGGAGGAAAUCAAUGAAACAAACAACAGAAAAGCAAUAGAGACAAUGAAGCCAACCUGGCUAUUUGAGAAGAUAAUAACAUUGUUAAAAUUCUGUCAUAUUAAUCAGUCAAAAGAAGAGAGAAGACAAAUUACCAAAUUAGGAAUGACAGAGGUCUCAUCUCUACAGAUUCUAUAGAUCUUAAAAAAAGGGGAUUAUUAUAAGUAACUUUAUACAUAUAAGCUUUACAAUUUACAUGAAAGGGAUAAAUAGAUAAGUUGAUUUGUAUAUCAUUAAAGAAAUUGUAUUUGUAGUUAAAAACCAGCAAGCGAAGUGUAAAGAAAAGAACAUUCUAGACAGACAGACAUAUCCCAAGAUACACAGAAAUACCAAGCAUAGAGCUACACUGUAUAGUAUGGUGACCACUAGCUAUAUGUGACAAUUUAAAUUUAAAUUAAUUAUAAUUCAGUAAAAUAAAUUUUGUACCUGUUACAUUUGCCACAUUUUAAGUUAUCAUUUACCUACAUGUGACUGGUAUUAUGUAGAACAUAAAGAACAUUCACAUCAACAAAGUUCUACUGGACAGAGCCAUCAUAAUGUGUUUAGGAAACUUCAGGAGUUCUGAUUUGAUGAGAGUGUAGGUUGCAAUGGUGAGAUGGAAGUUGCAAAGGCAAGUUGGAAGGGAAUUAUGCUGGAAGGGCAAACUGAUUCCAAACCAUUGAGUGUCUUCAGUGGCAAUGGUGUUUGGAUUUACCCUAGGGGACACCAGCUAGGGUAGAGAGGUGAUUUUUGGUUUUGGUUAGUGACGGUAGAUGCUGGUAGGGUAAGUUGAUCUGAUUUGUGUUUGUUUGGUUUUGAUUAGUGAAGGUAGAUGCUGGUGAGUUGAUCUGAUUUUGAGUAUAAUAUUUUGGAAUAUUAUACUCAAUAUAAUGUUUUGAAAUAAUAUUUUGAAAUAAUAUUUCUGGGGGCAGGAUAAAAGGUAGAUUUGAGGGGUGAAAUCAGUAUUCAGGAGCUCACUCUCUAACAGCCAAGUUGUCCAGAUGAGAGUGGUGGUAAGGACUAAGCUAUAAUGAGGCAAUGAGCAUAUAAGGAAGGAGACAUUUGAAUGCUAUUUAGAGGAAAAAAAGAUAGGAGGAUUUGAUGUGGGAGCUAACAGAAUCUGAAUGACCCUGAUUUCUGGAUUGAGCAUAUAGAGACAAGAUAGGACUUAUGUGGGGAAAAGCAGACUUUGAAAAGAGAAAACGAGUAUGACUAUACAUUUGGCCACAUUAUCUUUAAAGAUAGGCCCAAUUUAAUUAAGAGUCUGGAGUUGGUAAAACUCAGGAUCAGAUAUGUGCUUUUGGGCAUCACCAGAAUAUAGUUGGCUUUUUGAAGCUUUGAAUUUGGAUAAGAUUGCCCAGAGAGAAUAUGCAGCAUGUACAGAUCAAAGCCAAGGACACACCCCAAUAUUUAUUAGGUAUAGAAAGAUAGGACCUUAGAAUAAGAAUGAAAAUGAGUAACUAGAGAAAAAAAAAUAAAGAGUGGUUCCCAAAAGAACCCAAAGAAGAUAACAUUUCAAGGAGGGUUGCUGGUCCAGAGAAGUCAUAUAAAAGAACCAUAAGCAUAUAUUGGAUUUGUUGAACAGGAAGUCAUUUGGGACCUUUCAGAAGUGUAGUAUCCUGAAACACCAAGCAAAUUCAGACCUUCAUGCUGAGGUGAAUUUGUAAAGGGUCAUUGGGCGUACCCUUUGGGAGAACUGAUACGGCCUUCAGACCUUUGACCAAAACAGAUAAAAUAAACACAGAAAGACAUACCAAGAAUGACUUAAAGGGAGGAAGCAAAGGAGUCCAAUAAUGUAUUACAUUUCAACAUAAAGGAGAAGGAUGGGCCUCCUCUCACUGGUGUGAAAGAGGGUUCUUAGAGAUGAUUGAUACGCAUACCGUAAGUAUGUUCCCUGGACCAGCAACAUCAGCAUUACUCAGAAGCUUGUUAGACCCUACCUCAGAUCUACUGGAUCAGAAUUUGCUUUCCAACAAGACCCACAGAGAUCCUGAAUUAAUUUACUUUUGAGUAUUGACCACCAGAUUGUACCAUUGAAAGAUGCAUUUUCUUCUUUGCUGGGCCUCUCUACAUUUAGUUCUGUAUUAGGUCAAGAUUACUAAGUGCCAGUCCAAGCAUCCCAGGUGUCAGAGACAAGGGUGAGGUGAAGUGGUGGGGGUGAACUCUGAUAGGCCAGGGGAAUUAUUUCAGUUAAAAUAAUCUUUCCUUACUUUGGCAGCCUCUUAGUAGUAUAUCCUAUCUCCGGCCCUUCCACUCUCCACCUGUGAUUUGUCUCUCACACAGUUUUUAUUCUUUCACUCAUCCCCUUAUUCAUUCUGCUCUUAUCUUUACUUUUACUUAUCUAUCUAAUGCAUUUUAGUGUUAAGAUUUUAAGCUUUACUACAUGAUUAUUUUCCACAACCAUUUCAGCUAAUUAAUGUGAUAGUUAGGUUUUGAUGUAAUCUUGCUUAAUACUAAUUUAUAUUUAUUUAUUUGUGCUACCUCAUGAAGACUUAUUUCUUUGAAAAGGUUGCAAUGACUGCUCUGUCUUCCACUUCUUAAAAGGUGGUUAGGCAGACUACAGUGUCUAAAUUUGUGUCAUGGUUUGGUGUACACUUUCCCUUAAGUUUGGUUUUCAACAUCUAUUUCAUUCUUUUCUGUCAUUCGGCCAGGAUUGAGUUAAAUAUAUGUUCUUUUUCAUUGUACCCCCCAAAUCAUUGAGAAGGACGUUUUGUCCGCAUUUUCCUAACAUAAAUCUUUCUCUCCAGAUGGAAGAUUGAAGUCUCAUUGUGCUAAGGAGGAAGGAAGUGGGGGGGGGGUGCAUUUAGAAAUCUGCUAUAUCAAGAAAGACAUUAAAAAUUGAUAAAGCUACAGUAUAGAGAAUGCCAAGAACUUCUAAGCCUGUAUCAGAAAUAUUUAUCAGAACAACAGGAGAAGCUCACCAUGUCUCUCUCAGAACUUGGUGCUGCUAGAAUGCAGGAACAGCAGGUAUCCAGUAGAAAAAGCACUCUCCAGUGUUCAUCUGUGGAACUGGAUGGUUCCUACUUGAGCAUAGCCAGACCACAGACCUACUAUCAAACCAAGCAAAGACCUAAGUCUGCAGUCCAGGAUUCAGCUUCAGAAUCCCUUAUAGCAUUUAGGAAUAAUUCUUUGAAACCAGUAACCCUUCAUCAUCCCAAAGAUGAUCUAGAUAAGAUACCAUCAGAGACCACAACAUGUAAUUGUGAAUCUCCAGGGAGAAAACCUGCAGUCCCAACAGAGAAAAUGCCACAAGAAGAAUUGCACAUGAAGGAAUGUCCACAUCUUAAGCCUACUCCUAGUCAAUGCUGUGGUCAUAGACUUGCUGCAGAUCGUGUUCAUGACAGCCAUCCUACAAACAUGACCCCUCAACAUCCUAAGACACAUCCAGAAUCAUGCAGUUAUUGUCGGCUUUCUUGGGCAUCUCUGGUGCAUGGUGGUGGGGCACUGCAACCCAUUGAAACUUUGAAAAAGCAGAUCUCAGAAGAUAGAAAGCAGCAACUGAUGCUUCAGAAAAUGGAACUGGAAAUUGAAAAGGAGCGCCUUCAGCAUCUGCUGGCCCAGCAGGAGACAAAGCUUCUUCUAAAACAGCAGCAGCUUCACCAGUCUCGACUGGAUUACAAUUGGUUAAAAGCUCAGGCUCUGUUUAAGUCGAGAGAACUGGUUGCUGAAAAACAGCUUACUAAACCCCAAGAACUCAAACUGGAUAUGAAUGGCAGUGACUCUGGACCAAGUUUAUUGAAGUCAAACUGUGAUGGCUGGCUGCUUGGAACAUCAUCAUCUAUUAAAAAGCACCAAGACCCCCCAAACAGUGGAGAGAAUAGGAAGGAGAGGAAGACAGUUGGGUUUCAUUCGCAUAUGAAAGAUGAUGCCCAGUGGUCAUGUCAAAAGAAAGAUACAUGUAGACCCCAAAGAGGGACAGUGACAGGAGUUAGAAAAGAUGCGUCUACAUCUCCUAUGCCAACAGGAAGCCUAAAGGAUUUUGUCACCACAGCCUCACCAUCAUUACAGCACACCACCUCCCGGUAUGAGACAUCUUUGUUGGAUUUGGUUCAGUCUCUGAGCCCAAACUCUGCGCCCAAACCUCAGCGCUAUCCCUCCAGAGAAGCUGGGGCCUGGAAUCAUGGUACUUUCCGACUCAGUCCUCUAAAAUCAACCCGGAAGAAGAUGGGGAUGCACAGAACCCCUGAAGAGUUGGAGGAGAAUCAGAUUCUGGAAGAUAUAUUUUUCAUUUGACAUAUUGCAAAAUUUUCUUAGGAAAUUUGUGGGUUUCCUCACAUACUGAUCUAGGAUUUUAAAUUAUUUCAUUGCAAAGUAAUUGUGUCUCUCCUUUCACGGGGACUUGUCUCACUAGCAUCCUGUUACGUAUUGAAUAUAGAAAUCAUUCUAACAACCCAGGUUAUUUUCAAUCAGACCAGGCAUUCGAUAACACACUAAGGGGGUAGGAAUGGAAGAUGGUAUCUUUUAUAUGCUAAACAGAUUAGAAAAUUAACAUAGGAUACUUUCUGCGUGGUGGAAACCAUUGCAUAUUCAGCCUCAUUUCAAGAGUGUUUCCUUCUCAAACUUCUGCUAGAAAAUGCUGACUCACUUUUAUAUACAAGAAAAACCUUUCCACUGAAAAAUCCCUCUGAUUUAAAAGUAACCCCUUUGAAACAUAAGCAGUUUCAGAAAGGCAGACUCUCUCAUCUUUCUCAUCCUGUUCUCUCACUACUACAUUUCUGUAAGUGGUCCUUUAAUUCUGAAGUUGGAGUUGGUGCCCCUGCCAUCACAAACAACACGAGAGCCAAUUGUGAGUCAGUCUCAGUAGCCAUCAGCCUGGCAGCUGCCCAUCCCAUAACCAAAGAGCUCAAUGGGCUGGAGGGUGAGACCCAGCCAAUCCUUGGGAGCAAGCAGCACUAAAUCACAUCAGGGAGUGAUUAGUCCUGGGGAAAUUCAGUGGAGGCACAAGCCUGAAGCACUCUUCUACCAAUGUUUGGGUGACCACCCCUCCAAUAUCCCAGAAUGAAUAAGAACAAUCCCUAGGUAUUUUUAUUUACCCAAGUGUUCAGCUUAUUCACCCCACCCCCCCACCCCCCAUCACACGUGCUCCUGUGAACUUUCCAUGGUUAUGUCUACGGAAAAUGCCACUAGAGAGAGAGUGAUGCAAGCUGCUGCAAAGCUGAUGGGCUUCCUCUGGCCCUCCCUUUUCCUCCACGAGGAUUAAAGGAUACAAGCUGACCAGGCCUCACAGGUGCUCUGCUCGUGGCCCCAAAGAACCAUCUCUACUUGCCAGAGUAUGUUCCACCACCCAAGCAGGGUCUCCCUACUUUUUCUCACUGGCCUCGUUUUGACCCAGAGAAAGCCUAUGGAAGUUAUGCAGUGCAGACCUCAUCCUGUCUGCUGUCUUUUCUCCCACAGAGCUCUUGAGAUGGGUCCUUCAGCUUGCAGUGGUCCCUAGUAGCCUCUCAAGCUAAUGGGGAUGAUGAUCCUGGUUUAGCCAGAGUUCAAAACUCUCCAGUCAUUGAAAGCAAGGGGAGGGUGUGUUCCCAGAUGUGUAUUACUUGGGAAUUUUAUUUGAUCUGGAGGGUGUGGCUUUUUUUCUCUCCUUUUUACCAACCCCAACUAAACUGGGAGUAAGACUUAGUCAGUGUUGGUAGACAAAGUCAUACCACCCAGGGCAGCCUGCAUGCAGCGAGUCUGCGUGGCUUCCCUGAAUUACUCUUUUAAUUAAAACUAGAUUAUUUCAAUCUAGAAAAGCCUUGUUGAGCAGCCUCCUUAUCCAGAUAGAUCCAAAGCUCAUGUCUCUUCAGGCUGAGACUGGCGCUGUCACCUCCACCCAGCCUUCUUUCACUUGGGGUUUUUUAUUCUUUGGAGUAGAAAAGAAUGGAGCCCACUAAUAUUAUAUUUUUCUUCUGAAAUAAAUAUAAAGUCAAGACUAACUAGUUAUAAUCAUUCCCUUAAAAAGUUGGAAAAUCAUUACAGAUUAAAAUUUCUUUAUAAAGUUCACCUCUGAGAGUAACCAAAUCGGUUUCAUCCCAUAUCAAAAAGCCUUUGGAGUGUGGAGCUUUCUGUGGUAUGGCAGAAAUGGGUGGAUGGCAAACUAAGAGCCCUCAGCCAUUUUUUCAGUUAAAGUUAGGUUGCCAGAACUUUCUUUUCCUUGCCCCCUGUGUCAUGACUAGCUUAAGUGUACUUGACUCCCAUAGACUACUCCCAUGCCCACAGUCACCCAUUCCAGACUCCAGUGUCCUUAAAACUCUGGAGUGAGAGGAUGCCAGAGGAUCAAGAAAAGGAUCACAGUUUCUUGAAGAAGCUUGUUUGCCUUUAGAAGAAUCGUAAACAGAGUCUAAACUAAAGGCUUUUUGGGGGUCACAGCCACAGAGUGGAGUUUUAUUGCUUCUUUGCCUCUCCAUGAAUGGCCAAUUUGGAAAAGCAGAGAUGGGCUUUCAGCAGAAUAUCAACCAAUACAUUUUUCACAUGCAAAACUCAUCACCAGUUGCCUUUUUCUAACUUAAUGGACAUUUUGUUGGUGUUGGUGCAAGGGCAAUAGGAUGUAAAUUUGUAUAUAAUCUAAUGUCUUCAUUAUUAAUUGAAUAGUACAUGUUAACAUUUUAAUCUAUUUAAAUUUACUUUGAAAUAUAUACAUACAUAUGAAUGAAAGGUUGUUACAGAGCCUCAAAGCUGUUGCAGACUAUCCCAAGAGAAAGGAUCUGGCACAAAGGAAUCUGCCUUUCCUCCGUCUCAAGUCUCCCACCCUUGACUGGUUGGGAUUUGCUCGUCCAGCCUCUAGACACUUCCCAAAGCAAGACUGGACACAUGCCGAGGGCGUUGCGGAUAGUGCCUCACCAUUGCCCACCCUGCUGCCCAACUCCUGUGAGAGAAAAACCAAUCAAUGUUUACAAAAUGGAAAAGGACACAGCAUGUCCUUUGAACUCCCUAAGUAAGGCCCACAGUUCUUGAUGCAGAGAACCAAAGUGAAUCAUAGAAAAGCUUUUGCUAACAGUCCGCUUUCCAGGAGGCAAACUUGUGUUUAUCCAAACCUGAUCCCCAUGAUGGGGACUUUUCUAGAGCACCCCAAAUGUCAUGGGGAGAGAGGGACUCUUUCUGCUCCCUCAGAGCUACUCUUCACUUGUCCCUGCUUCCGGCACCAAGUUCAUAAUAGAGAUCUUCUGGCCAGAGAAUCAGGGGAGAGGAGAGGCCUGAUGGGGCAGAGCUGGACGAAGUCUGCUAAGAGAGAUGGAGGCUGUGGCGGACUCCUUCCAACUCACGAUUUAUCCUCAGCUCAGAGUGUAUUUUGAAUAUGAGCAAAUGUUUAUGUACGUAUGAGAUUUCAAGUUAAUAAAUCAUCUCUAUGGCUAUUUUCCCCA